CAUUUGUCUCUUGCUGCAGCUGGUGCUCCAAAUCUGGUCUUAGCUGCUUCGUGUCUUCUUCUCCAGCCUCUGUGGCCCUGUGACCUGCAGGUAUUGGGAGAUCCACAGCUGAGGGACCCCCGGAAGCCUAGAAAUGGGACCAUUGGAAUUUAGAGAUGUGGCCAUAGAAUUCUCUCUGGAGGAGUGGCAUUGCCUGGACACUGCACAGCAGAAUUUAUAUAGGGAUGUGAUGUUAGAGAACUACAGACACCUGGUCUUCCUUGGUAUUGUUGUCACUAAGCCAGACCUGAUCACCUGUCUGGAGCAAGGAAAAAAACCCUUCACUGUGAAGAGACAUGAGAUGAUUGCCAAAUCCCCAGUUAUGUGUUUUCAUUUUGCCCAAGACCUUUGUCCAGAGCAGAGCCUAAAAGAUUCCUUCCAAAAAGUGAUAGUGACAAGAUAUGAAAAACGUGAAUAUGGCAAUUUAGAGUUAAAAAAAGGUUGUGAAAGUGUGGAUGAGGGUAAAGUACACAAAAGAGGUUAUAAUGGACUUAACCAAUGUUUGACAGCUACCCAGAGCAAAGUAUUUCAAUGUGAUACAUAUGUGAAAGUCUCUCAUAUAUUUUCAAAUUCAAACAGACAUAAGAUAAGAGAUACUGGAAAAAAACCUUUCAAAUGUAUAGAAUGUGGCAAAGCUUUCAACCAGUCCUCAACCCUUGCUACACAUAAGAAAAUUCAUACUGGAGAGAUAACCUGCAAAUGUGAAGAAUGUGGCAAAGCCUUCAACAGGUCCUCACACCUUACUUCACAUAAGAGAAUUCAUACUGGAGAGAAACGGUACAAAUGUGAAGAUUGUGGCAAAGAAUUAAAGUAUUCCUCUACCCUUACUGCACAUAAGAGAAUUCAUACUGGAGAGAAACGGUACAAAUGUGAAGAUUGUGGCAAAGAAUUAAAGUAUUCCUCUACCCUUACUGCACAUAAGAGAAUUCAUACUGGAGAGAAACCCUACAAGUGUGAUAAAUGUGGCAGAGCAUUUAUUUCAUCCUCGAUCCUUUAUGUACAUAAGAUAAGUCAUACUGAAGAGAAACCCUACAAAUGUGAAGAAUGUGGCAAAGCCUUCAAGCUCUCCUCAAUCCUUAGUACACAUAAGAGAAUCCAUACUGGAGAGAAACCCUACAAAUGUGAAGAAUGUGGCAAAGCCUUCAGGCGCUCCUUAGUCCUUCGUACACAUAAGAGAAUUCAUACUGGAGAGAAACCCUACAAGUGUGAUAAAUGUGGCAAAGCAUUUAUUUCAUCCUCACUCCUUUAUAAACAUAAGAUAAGUCAUAGUGAAAAGAAACCCUACAAAUGUGAAGAAUGUGGCAAAGCCUUCAAGCGCUCCUCAACACUUACUAUACAUAAGAUAAGUCAUACUGAAGAGAAACCCUACAAAUGUCAAGAAUGUGACAAAGUCUUCAAACGCUCCUCAGCCCUUAGCACACAUAAGAUAAUUCAUAGUGGAGAGAAACCCUACAAAUGUGAAGAAUGUGGCAAAGCCUUCAAGCGCUCCUCAAACCUUACUACACAUAAGAUAAGUCAUACUGAAGAGAAACUCUACAAAUGUCAAGAAUGUGACAAAGCCUUCAAGUACUCCUCAGCCCUUAGCACACAUAAGAUAAUUCACAGUGGAGAGAAUCCCUACAAAUGUGAAGAAUGUGGCAAAGCCUUCAAGCGCUCCUCAGUCCUUAGUAAACAUAAGAUAAUUCAUACUGGAGCGAAACCCUACAAAUGUGAAGAAUGUGGCAAAGCCUUUAAGCGCUCCUCACAGCUUACUAGUCAUAAGAUAAGUCAUACUGGAGAGAAACCCUACAAAUGUGAAGAAUGUGGCAAAGCUUUUAACUUGUCCUCAGACCUUAAUACACAUAAGAGGAUUCAUAUUGGACAGAAAGCCUACAUAGUGAAGAACAUGGCAAAUCUUUGAAAUAUUCCUCAACCCUUAAUAAACAUAAGAUAAUUCAUACUGGAGAGAAACCGUAUAAAUGUGAUGACUGUUGGAAAGCCUUUGACCACCCCUCUACUCUUACUAAAUAUGAGAAUUUAUAUGAAACAUAACUCCUACAAAAAUAAAGAAUGUGACAAAUCAUUUUAAGGAAGUUCUCAACCCUUACUACACAUAAUUCAUACUGGACGGAAACUCUACAGGUGUGAAAAAUGCAGCAAAGCCUAUAACAAGUUCUCAAUUCUUUUUUUUUUUUUUUAAGAAGGAGUUUCAUGCUUCUCACCCAGCCUGGAGUGCAAUGGCACGAUCUCUGCUCACUGCAACCUCUUCCUCCUGGUUCAAGCCAUUAACCUGCUUCAGCCUCCACCACCAUGCCCAACUAAUUUUUGUAUUUUUGGUAGAGACAGGGUUUUGCCAUAUUUAACAGGCUGGUCUCCAACUGUGAUUCACACACCUUGGCCUCCUAAAAUGCUGGGAUUACAGUCAUGAGCAUCCAUGCCCAGCCACAAGUUCUCAGUUCUUAAGAGACAUGGUGAUAAUUCAUGCUGAAGAGGAACUUUACAAACUUGAAAGAUGUGACAGUGCUUUUACCACCACCUCCAACUUUUCUGUACAUAAAGAUGAUUAUACUAGUGUGAAACCCUAGAAAUAAUAGAAAAUUUGACAAAUCCUUUAUAUGGUUGCAAGACUUGAUUGUAGGUAAGAUAAUUCAUACUGGCAAAACUCCUACAAGUGUGAAGAAUGUGGGAAAACUUUUUAAUCAGUGCAUACACCUUAUUUCACAGGAAAGCUAGUAUCCUUGAGAAAAAUUGCACAAUUAUAAAAAAUAUGGAAAACCCAUUAAUGCCUACUCACAUCUUACCCAACAGAAGGUGGUUCACAGUUAAUGAAAGCAUUUAAAGUGCAAUUAUGCUCAAGAAAUCUUUCAGAAAAUAGAAGCCUUUAAAGUGAAGAAGAGUAUUCUGAAGACAACCAUUACACAUAUAAAGGGGGUUGUAUUACCUUUACUUGCAUCACAGAUUUCAUUGCACACAUUUUGUACUAGAGGAAAACCCUGAAGCAGUUGCUCCAGCUUUGUUCAACAACAGGGAAUUUAUGUUAGAGAAGAAUCCUGCAAAUGUAGUGAAUUUGGAAACAAAUUUUUUUUCAAAAACUACAGCUUAGAAAACACCAGAGAGUUGAUACUAAAAUAUAUGUUUGCAGAAACAGUAAAUAUAAAAAAUAUUUAAUUCAAAAUGAAUUCCAUGUAAAUAUCAGAGAAUUUACAGUAGAAUAAGGCACUGAUACUUCAGACAUUACACUAAAACAGUGUUGAGUAUAAAAAAGAAUCCACAACAAAAAUUGUUAGAUAAAUUAUAUAUAGCUUUAAAAGGUUUUUUGAAGCAUUGUAAUUACAUUGAAAGUAUACUUGCUUUCUUGAGAAAAAAUUUUUGAAAAGUGAAUAAGGUAAUAGAGCUUUCAAAUUUAUGCUGUUACUUUAUUUCUAUUCACAUGUGAAAGCAUGUGAUCAAUUGAUGCUGCAUCAGAGAUAUUACAGAUUCUUUAUUGGGCAUUCCUUAUAACCUUUUCUAUUAAAGAGAAAGGAUAUUAAAAUGUAAGAUGCAUGAUGAAAAUAUAAGUGGACAGGCUGUUCGUAUUUGACCUAUAUUAAGUAAUGUAUAAGGUAGUGUUCAGAGUAAUACUUUUCUACAUUAUAGUGAGAGAAAUUAUGAAUUACAGUUAAAGGUAUAUUAAAUUACUGUAUUAUUUUACUAAUUUUAUGUAAUAAAAUACACUACAUUAAAAAA